GUUGCCCAGGGCAACCGCUCCUUCAGGCGUGAAUGUGGCGGCUGCCUCUGCGAAUGGACGGCGUGGGAAGAGAAUGGCUUCUGCAAGGAAAGCCAGCCGUCCCAUGCGUGAUGUUUUUGGUGACUUCAGUGAUGUUUCCUUGGAAGAUUCAACAAUGGAAGAAAUCAGAAACUUCCAGAUCAGUAGAAAUCUUACCAAAAUAGCACCUGGUCAUAGCAGAUUUCUAAAAAGAAACCAAACUCUAGAUGAGAAACACUUACUCCUGAAAGAGAACCCUGUGCUCGGGAGUGGACCCAGGCUUGCCUCAUGUAGACCGCCCACCACUGCCUCCAGGAUCCGAGCCAAUGCCGCACUCAUGAAGCUGGCCCAGCUGGAAACCCGGAUCAUGAAUCGGAAGCUGCAGAGGAAUUUGUCUGACACGGAAUCUGACUCAAUGACCGCCGAUGCUGGUCUUCCAAAGAGAGCUGACAGAAUCCUCUCUGGGGGUGCACUCGAACUCGCGUCCCAGAACACAGACAAAACUUCCCAGAAUCAAGCCCGUGAACUUCCUGUCACCGAAAAUAAUGCACAGAACGCGAAGGUCAGUAGGUUUCUAAAGAAGAAACAAGCACCUGUUGAAAACAUAUCCCCUGAAGCACCUGCUGGGAAAGAGAGGACUUUGCAAACCCCCAAACAGAAAGAACCUGCUAGAACAUUUGAUUCUCCAGACAGUGACGAAGAAGAAAUGAAAGUAUUGCUAGGAAGCUUGAUGGACUCUUCUAGAGAAAAAAACACGAAUCAAGGCUUCAGCAGCGCUAACGUCAGCGAGGAAGAAGAAAGAAAACUAUUUUCGGUCCCAUCUCAACUGAGAGCAUUUACUGUACCCAGCGUGGAACUCUCCAGCGCAAAGCCUUCUCAGACAUCACACCUGCCAACCUCCCUGGCAGCAGACAGAACCCUUCACAGCACUCGCUCAAGAGCAGACUACCCACAGAGUCACGUUUCCAGUGACACCGCCUCCCACACGCCGUCAGUUUCCAUCACAGGCGCCUUUUCAAACUCAGUGUCUUUAAAGAUGGGGCAUGUCAAGCUUGUGUCCUCCCCGGGAAGGAGUGAGGCUGAGACUGUGGACGAGCCAGUCUCAGAAGGUGCUGAUGACAGCCUCGACGAGUUUAGAAUAAAUAUUUUAUCGCUUGACGGUCUGGCUCCAGCUGUCAGUGAGAACUCCGAUUUGGAACAGGAAGAGGAAAGUGCUCAGAGACAAAAAACAGCUGGCAAAAUCUUCAGAGCCGAGGCGUCCACUGGGCAGGAUGCCCCGAGGCAGGCCCAGGCGAGGAGCUGGGCAUCACAGGGAAAGGCCGCCUCUGCAGAGGGGGAUGAGAGCGAGGUCUCGGAGCAUCUCAGUGCCAGCUCGGCUUCUGCCAUCCAGCAGGACAGCACUUCCAGCAUGCAGCCACCAUCUGAAGCCCCCAUGGUGAACACAGUCAGCUCAGCUUAUUCGGAGGAUUUUGAAAACUCUCCAAGUCUGACAGCAUCUGAGCCAACCGCCCAUUCCAAGGAGUCUCUUGACAGAACACUGGACGCUUUGUCUGAAUCCUCUUCAAGUGUGAAGACAGACCUUCCACAAACAGCCGAGUCUAGGAAAAAGUCGGGCAGGCACGUGACAAGAGUGCUUGUGAAGGACACAGCUGUGCAGACGCCAGAUCCUGCCUUCACCUACGAGUGGACCAAGGGCUGGAGUGUAGUGGUGCGAUCUUGGCUUACUGCAACCUCCACCUCCUGGGUUCAAGCGAUUCUCCUGCCUCAGCCUCCUGAAUAGCUGGGAUUACAGGUAUGUGCCACCACGCCCAGAUAAUUUUUGUAUUUUUAGUAGAGAUGGGGUUUCACCAUGCUGGCCAGGCUGGUCUCAAAUUCCUGACCUCGUGAUCUGCCUGCCUCGGCCUCUCAAAGUGCUGGGAUUAUAGGUGUGAGCCACCGCACCUGGCCCCCUGUAUAAUUUUAAAAUGUUCUUUGUAGAGACAGGGUCUCCCUAUGUUCCCCAGCCUGGUCUUGAACUCCUGGGCUCAAGUGAUCCUUCCACCUGCUCAUGUUGGCCCCCCAAGGUGCUGGGACUACAGGCAUGAGCCACCAUGCCUGGCCUUCGGGCAUUUCUCUCAUUCCCAGCUUCAGUCUCGGCUCUUGCUGGUGGAAAGGCCCCAUUCUUUUAAACAUUCCCAUGUUAUUAUUUUAUUUUAUAUAAUUUUAUUUUAUGAGAUGGGGUCUCGCUCUGUUGCCCAGGCUGGAGUGCGGUGGCACAAUCUCGGCCCACUGCCUCCUCCACCUCCUGGGUUUCAGCGAUUCUCCCACCUCAGCCUCCCCAAUAGCUGGGACUAGAGGCGCCUGGCUAAUAAACAUUCCCUUUUAAUAUCUCUUUUCUCAUCCAUAUGGCUCUUGACAAGGUAGACUGGAUGUGAAAAAUGAUGUAGUUCCCAGCCUGGCCAAUAUGGUGAAACCCCGUCUCUACUAAAAAUACAAAAAUUAGCCUGGUGUGGUGGCACGCAUCUGUAGUCCUAGCUACUCGGGAGGCCGAGGCACAAGAAUCGCUUGAAACCAGAAGGUGGAGGUUGCAGUGAGCUGAGAUCGUGCCAUAGCACCCCAGCCUGGGCGACAGAGUGAGACUCUGUCUCAAAAAAAAAAAAAAAAAAAAAAAAAGGCAAUGUAAUUCUCACUGGAUCUAUUUGUUUUGAUUUGGGGGCUUAACCUAACAUCAGCCUGACGGGCCCCCCAGGAGAGGGUGAGUGGUGUCUGUUUCUCAGGAGGGAAAGUCAAUCACAUGGACUGAGUCAAAUCACCUUGGAGGUGUUAAAUGGUAUUUUCAACCUGGGAUCUGGGCUCAGAAUUGUUUGUGUCUCUCUGCACUUCUGUCCAUAUUUUUGGCAAUUUAGGGAUGCUUUCAUGAAACACUGGCGAGGCUGUUUUCCUAGACUAGGACUGACAGGGAAAGGAGAAAGAAAAAACAGCAGCCAUAAACACGCUGGCCUCAGAGCCCAGAGAACACGCAACAUCCUGAGGUCAACAGUGACCCUUAGAAGAAGGGCUGGGAAAGCACAUCCUCCACUGCUCUCGACUGCAGCCACCGUGAGCCGGAGCCACCGCUGCACCCAGCUAGGAUACCCGUGCCUUGAGCCAAGAAAACCUAGCAGAAAAAUGGAGGCAGCCUUGGGAAAUACUUGAAAGGGGAAGAGGGUAAAAAAAAGUAAAGAAGGGCCGGGUGCGGUGGCUUACACCUCAGCACUUUCAGAGGCUGAGGCAGGAGGAUUGCUUGAGCCUAGGAGUUCAAGACCAGCCUGGGCAACAUAGGGAGACCCUGUCUCUACAAAAAAUUUUAAAAAUUAGCCAGGCGUGGUGGCGCACCUGUAGUCCCAGCUACUUGGGAGACAGAUGGGAGGAUUACGUGAGCCCAGGAGGCUGUAGUGAGCUGUGAUCAUGCCGUGCACUCCAGACUGGGCAAUAGAGCAAGACCCUGUCUCAAACCAAAAAAAAAAAAAAAAAAUGCAAGAGUGGCGAUCACCUUCAGAAAGAGGGAAGAACAAGGUCACGUAGUUUAUUCCAGGGUCGUAUCUGUGGACCCGAAAGUCAUUUCUCUGCGUCCUGCCUGCUUACCCCUCUCUUUGUCCCC